ACCGUGGCAACGGACGGCAACAGCUCGGGCGGCGCAUGGAGAGUGCGGGCGGCUUCAAGCUGGGUAUGGAGCCCCUCAGCGGCGGCGGGGUCUGUGAGUUGGACGCGGGGUCUUGGCGGGGAAUGGAGGUAGAAUAAACGUGGGACCCGGAGUGCACCAAGGUGAGAAAAAAAAAUUACUAAAAAUGACAAGUAGAAGACUUGAGGAGUCCAUGGGGGCUGUUCAGAUGGGAUUGGUCAAUAUGUUCAAAGGAUUUCAAAGCAAGGUUUUGCCACCCCUGAGUCCAAAGGUGGUUACAGAAGAAGAAGUAAACCGAAUGCUUACACCCUCAGAGUUCCUGAAGGAAAUGUCCCUGACCACCGAGCAGAGACUGGCAAAAACACGUUUGAUGUGCCGACCACAGAUCAUCGAACUCUUAGAUAUGGGGGAAACAACACAUCAGAAGUUUUCAGGAAUUGACCUGGAUCAGGCAUUAUUCCAGCCCUUUCCAUCAGAAAUUAUAUUUCAGAACUACACUCCCUGUGAAGUCUAUGAAGUUCCACUGAUUUUGAGGAACAAUGACAAAAUUCCAAGGUUGGUGAAAGUUGUGGAAGAAAGUUCGCCUUACUUUAAAGUAAUCAGCCCCAAAGAUAUUGGCCACAAAGUGGCUCCUGGAGUGCCUUCCAUAUUCCGAAUCCUCUUUACUCCAGAGGAGAACAAGGAUUACGCCCAUACGUUGACCUGUGUUACUGAAAGAGAAAAGUUUAUUGUACCCAUCAAAGCUAGAGGGGCACGAGCCAUUCUCGAUUUUCCUGACAAGCUGAAUUUUUCCACUUGUCCUGUCAAAUACAGCACCCAGAAGAUUCUGCUGGUACGAAACAUUGGCAACAAAAAUGCUGUAUUUCACAUCAAAACUUGUAGGCCUUUCUCUAUAGAACCAGCUAUUGGAACUCUUAAUGUGGGAGAGUCCAUGCAACUGGAAGUGGAGUUUGAGCCACAGAGUGUGGGCGAUCACAGUGGAAGACUUAUCGUGUGUUAUGACACAGGUGAAAAGGUGUUUGUAUCUCUCUAUGGAGCUGCCAUAGACAUGAAUAUAAGGCUGGAUAA